ACCCGGAAGAGCCGUCAACUUAGCGAGCGCAACAGGCUGCCGCUGAGGAGCUGGAGCUGGUGGGGACUGGGCCGCAAUGGACAAGCUGAAGAAGGUGCUGAGCGGGCAGGACACGGAGGACCGGAGCGGCCUGUCCGAGGUUGUUGAGGCAUCUUCAUUAAGCUGGAGUACCAGGAUAAAAGGCUUCAUUGCGUGUUUUGCUAUAGGAAUUCUCUGCUCACUGCUGGGUACUGUUCUGCUGUGGGUGCCCAGGAAGGGACUACACCUCUUCGCAGUGUUUUAUACCUUUGGUAAUAUCGCAUCAAUUGGGAGUACCAUCUUCCUCAUGGGACCAGUGAAACAGCUGAAGCGAAUGUUUGAGCCUACUCGUUUGAUUGCAACUAUCAUGGUGCUGUUGUGUUUUGCACUUACCCUGUGUUCUGCCUUUUGGUGGCAUAACAAGGGACUUGCACUUAUCUUCUGCAUUUUGCAGUCUUUGGCAUUGACGUGGUACAGCCUUUCCUUCAUACCAUUUGCAAGGGAUGCUGUGAAGAAGUGUUUUGCCGUGUGUCUUGCAUAAUUCAUGGCCAGUUUUAUGAAGCUUUGGAAGGCACUAUGGACAGAAGCUGGUGGACAGUUUUGUAACUAUCUUCGAAACCUCUGUCUUACAGACAUGUGCCUUUUAUCUUGCAGCAAUGUGUUGCUUGUGAUUCGAACAUUUGAGGGUUACUUUUGGAAGCAACAAUACAUUCUCGAACCUGAAUGUCAGUAGCACAGGAUGAGAAGUGGGUUCUGUAUCUUGUGGAGUGGAAUCUUCCUCAUGUACCUGUUUCCUCUCUGGAUGUUGUCCCACUGAAUUCCCAUGAAUACAAACCUAUUCAGCAACAGCACAUAAGCCUUGGGUGCAAGUGAUUCCCAGGUGGCAAAAGGCAGCCCCAUCAGAGAUCACGGGAGCAACAGUAAGGGACAGAGUUUUGGGGUCCACUUGUCCCUCAGCAUGGAAGCCAUCACCGUGGUCCUGCAUAGAGUGAGUCUGCUUCUACUCUGGCAUCUGAGAACAAGUGACUCUGCUUUAGACAAGCCCCUGGAGAGCCUGGCCAUGGAGUGAGGUAGAAAAGAAGCACUUUUUGGUGGUAUAUGCUGUUUCUGAAUUUGAAUCUAAGCAUUCUUGGUGUUCUGAUUCUGCGCCUGACUGUGGAAUGUAUUUUCUGACAUUAGGUGCAGACUCUUUUUCUCUUGGGUUUUAUUUCCCAUCCCUCCCUCCCUCUCCCUGCAUAUCUUUCUUUAUGACCUCCUGGCACUAGAUGGGGAAAGAACAGAGCAGCAGCAGAAAAUGCUGCUGUUUUUUUUUUGGACGAGAGCCCAUAGGAGUUGAAAAAUCCUGCUGCUCUCAGCUAUAUUUUUUUCUCCAUUAUUUAUAAAUGUUUGCUUUUAAACUGAUUUUAUUUUCCAUUCUCCCCUGGAGUUGGGCCAGGGGAGAGUGGGGUGGGAAGACAGAUCCCUGCUGUGCAGCCAGCAGGAAGUAGGCACGCCUGCCCAGUGACCUUUAAAUAGUCCCAGUGUUUGCACUUAGCCUGUGCUGGGGACACUGGGGAUAAACUGCAGGUGGUCUCAUGUCAGCCUGAUGCCUAACCUACAAAGUGCUUUUGUGUCCACGAUCUUACCUGGUUCUUAUGGAGAGCCUUGUGAGGAAGCAGGGAUUGUUAUACCACUGUGCAGUCAAGGGAAUCAAGGCCCACACUGGUUUUUGGAUCCACCCAAAGCCACAGCUUCAGCCUCCUUCAUGACCCCAGAGUUUCCUGGCCUGUUUCUGGUUGUGCCUCCUGUAACUGCCUGUGACUGUUUCCCUCGUUUUCAUCAGCCAAGCCAUCUCCUCCCUGGCCCUCCCUGCCCAUCUCUUUUGGAAGCUUCUUCCUGGAUCUGCAGGAUGUUCACUGUCCCUUGUGUUCCCUUUCAGCUCCUCCUUGUUGCCUGACUACGAUUAGUGCCCUGUCUUGUCAGCCAGCAUUCCUGGCCCUCCAGGACCUCCAGAGUCAUCCUACAAAUGACGUUUAUCUGGAUUGCCUUUCUGUUCUUUGCACAGGGCCAACUGGUCCACUAGGGCUCCUCCUCUGUCACUGCUAAACCAAAGGAAGUGGCCUGCUGGUUGUCCCCUUUCUUGUGGCUAAUUGCUGAACCUUUCUUUGUCCUACUGUGGCUAAGAACUCUGACUGGUUUUUUUUUUUUUUUCUUUUUGAGAUGGAGUCUCACUCCGUCGCCCAGGCUGGAGUGCAGUGGCGUGAUCUCUGCUCACUGCAACCUCCACCUCCCGGGUUCAAGCAAUUCUCCUGCCUCAGCCUUCCAAGUAGCUGGGAUUACAGGUGCCCGCCACCACGCCCGUGCUAAUUUUUGUGUUUUUAGUGGAGACAGGGUUUCACCAUGUUGGCCAAGCUGGUCUGGAACUCCUGACCUCAGGUAAUCCGCCCACCUUGACCUCCCAAAGUGCUGGGAUUACAGGUGUGAGCCACUGUGCCCUGCUGAUCUUUUCUUCUGAGGCUGGGGAGGUGUGAACAAGCCUGACGGGGCCAGAGAGAGGAGCUAGUCUUCCCAGGUUCUUUCUAGGCUAUUGAUGACAUCCAGUCAUCUGCUCAGGUCACUAACCUGUCCUCAGCCAGGAAAGGAAAUUUUAUGCUACCCCUCUGGCUUUUGUGGGAUUCUUUCACAUCCCAGGUGCCUCUUGGAGACAGAUCUCAGAAGGGCUGUGGUGUCAGAAGGGACAUGGAGGAGGUCAGGAGGGCUCAUGGUUCCUUUUCUUUAGAACUGAUACGAGGCUUGGCUAGUCACUGUGAGCUCCAGCAGCUCCAGCAGCCUGGAAUAAGACACCUAGAAGGCUCAUCCCUCCAUGUCCAUGUCCUUUUUUUUUUUUUAGAUUGAACAACCAUGCUUUGUUUAAAAAAUAAUCUCAGCAAACUAGGGAUACAAGAGAAUUUCCUCAACCUGUCGAAGGGCAUCUUUAAAAUAUCUACUGCUAACAUCCUAUGUAAUGAUGAAAGGCUGAAUGUUUUCCCCUAAGAUUGAGAAUAAGACAGAGAUGUCAACUCUUACCACUUCUAUUCAACGUUGUACUGAAAAUUCUAGCCACUGCAAUCAUGUUUUAAUUGGGAGUAGGGGGAAAGAGGGAGGGAAGGAGAAAAAUGAAAGGCCUUUAGAUUGAAAAGAAAUGAGUAAAACUGUCUAUUCACAGAUAUUAUCAUCUAUGUAGAAAACCAAAUCAAAUCCAUUACUAAGUUACUGAAACCAGCAAGUGAGUUUCGCAACACAGCAGGAUAUAUAAUUGAUAUACACAAAUCAAUUGUGUUUCUCCAUGUUAGAAGUAAAGAAUUAGGAAUUGAAAAUUUAAAAAUAAUACCAUUUACAAUAGCAUUAAAAUAUAAAAUUCUUGGGAAUAAACCCGACAAACUAUGUGGAUUAUCUGUACACUGAUAACUAAAAAGCAUUGCUAAGAAAAAUUAAGACCUAAGUAAAUAUCUUGUUGAUAGGUUGAGAGACUCAACAUUGUUGAUGUUAAUUCUUUCCCAUAUUAAUCUAUAGAUAUAAUGCAGUCCCCAUCCAAAGCCAAGCAGGCUUUUUUUUUUUUUUUUUUGUAGAAAUUAAAAACUGGUUUUAAGAUUCACAUGGCAUGCAGAUGAUCUAGAAGAUCCACAGUAACUCUCCUGCUGUGCAGCUGGUUCCUAACAGGUCAUGGACCUGUCCAUGGCCUGUAGGUUGGGAACCUCUGCUACAGAGGAUCCAGAUUUAAAUUCAGAAGAAGCUUCAUCUAUUUCUGUAGUUUCAUUUUCUUGCAAUAACUGCUGCAUCAAACUUGAACUUCGCAGGAUUUUCUGAAGCUGCUCAAUUUGGCCAUCUUGCUUUUUAAUUGUAUUUCUUAACACUAGAAUUUUCUAUUUCAAGUUUUUGUACGUGGCCUUGCGUCUCCUUAGUACAUUUUAUAGUCGCUGUAAGUUGAUUCCAUUUUUCUUGAAAUUGAAUUCUCAUCUGACCUAAUUUCUUCCUUGAAUCCUACAUCUCACUUUCUCAAUGGACGCAGUGACGCAAUGAAGCAUCCAGCAAAGCUUUUGUUGUUGAUUGUUUAGGACGUCACCCUGUUUUUGUUGAAGUUGUCUCACAACUACUUCUCUUUCUGCUUUCUCUCUUUCAUAUUGACAUUGUUUUUCUUUCAAAUGAUUAACUUUAUUGAUCAUCCUCUUGUUCUUCUAGCAAAAGACGGUGCUUUAUGCACUCAGCUUGAAGAUUUUGUGCUGUAGCAUCACAUUUGGCUUGACUAUCAAUUACUGUUUUUUCUUGAUUGUCAGCUUUGUUGUGAACAUCAUCCAGUUGCUGUUGAAGCAACAUAUUUUGUCUUCGUAGUUGACAUAAUCUUACUUGCUUUUCUGUGCAUUUUUCUACUUUAUCUUGGCCACUUGUGUACAUUUUUUCAAUGUCCUUCAUUUGACACCGUUUGGUUUAGCUCUCUUUGUAUGUGUUCAAAAACCAAAGCGUUUUCUUUCAGAGCCUCUCUUGUGUUAUGGAGCUCAGUUUUGAGGCACCUGGACUUACUCUCAGCUUUAGAAAGUUGCUGAGAAAGAAUCAGAACAUGAGAAUUCAAAUUUUCCUGUAAAUGACGCAAUUUAUCUACUGUGCCCUGGAAAUCAAGCUCUUGGUCUCUUUCUGUUGAGUGACUUUGAUCAUGAUCAUGUAGAGCAACAUUCAGUCUACGAUGGUAUGAUUCCAUUUCGUCAGUCUUUGCCUGCUUUGUUUUUCCUUCUCCAGUUUAGAACGGAGCAUUGUGUUCUCAUCUGUCAGAGCAGUAAGCUGUCCACUAUAAUGGGCUAUCGUUUUUGUUGAUUUUUCCCCAUUCUGUUUUAGAGCCUUUUGAAGGUCUUCAUGCUUUCUUUUUAUAAUUUCAAUGUCUUUUAAGUAUUUCUUUUCCAGGAUUUGAUUUUUUAUUGUGUGUAUUUCCAGCCUGAGCCUGGCAAUUUCAUCUUGCAUCAAAUGGUUUUUAUGCAACAGGUCUUCUUCUUUUUCAUGACUAUCAGAAAUCUCAAACUGCAGAGUUCUUGUUCCCAUUCAAGUUUUUGAUAUUCUGUGAUAUUUCUUUUUUUUCAGAUAGUCUCUUUUGUAGUACACUAGUCUUUUUCAUUUUUUAAUUUUUACUGUAAGUCACUCAGUGAUUAUCUUUAAGUUCCACUGAUCUUUUACAUAAAUAAACUGCAUUUUUAAUUUUCUUUUUUUAUAUGAGAUUCUGGAAAUACUUCUUUUUUUAAAUUAUACUUUAAGUUCUGGGGUACAUGUGCAGAACAUGCGGGUUUGUUACAUAGGUAUACAUGUAAUGUUAUCCCUCCCCUAGCCCCCACCCCCGGACAGGCCCCGGUAUGUGAUGUUCCCCUCCCUUUUCCAUGUGUUCUCAUUGUUCAACUCCCACUUAUGAGUGAGAACAUGUGGUGUUUGGUUUUCUGUUCUUGUGUUAGUUUGCUGAGAAUGAUGGUUUCCAGCUUCAUCCAUGUCCCUACAAAGGACAUGAACUCAUCCUUUUUUUAUGGCUGAAUACUAUUCCAUGGGUGUAUAUAUGCCACAUUUUCUUUAUCCAGUCUAUAAUUGAUGGACAUUUGGGUUGGUUCCAAGUCUUUGCUGUUGUGAACAAUGCUGCAGUAAACAUACAUGUGCAUGUGUCUUUAUAGUAGAAUGAUUUAUAACCCUUUGGGUAUAUACCCAGUAAUGAGAUUGCUGGGUUAAAUGGUAUUUCUAGUUCUAGAUCCUUGAGGAAUCGCCACACUGUCUUUCACAAUGGUUGAACUAAUUUACACUCCCACCAACAGUGUAAAAGUAUUCCUAUUUCUCCCUGUCCUUUCCAGCAUCUGUGGCCACCAUGCCACUUUUUAAUGAUUGCCAUUCUAACUGGCAUGAGAUGGCAUCUGAUGGUGGUUUUGAUUUGCAUUUCCCUAAUGACCAGUGAUGAUGAGCAUUUUUUCAUAUGUUUGUUGGCUGCAUAAAUAUCUUCUUUUGAGAAGUGUCUAUCCUUCGCCCACUUUUCGAUGGGGUUGUUUUGCUCUUAUAAAUUUGUUUAAGUUCUAUGUAGAUUCUGGAUCUUAGCCCUUUGUCAGAUGGAUAGAUUGCAAAAAUUUUCUCCCAUUCUGUAGGUUGCCUGUUCACUCUGAUGAUAGUUUCUUUUGCUGUGCAGAAGCUCUUUGGUUUAAUUAGAUCUCAUUUUGUCUAUUUUGGCUUUUGUUGCCAUUGCUUUUGGUGUUUUAGUCGUGAAGUCUUUGCCUAUGCCUAUGUCCUGAAUGGUAUUGCCUAGGUUUUCUUCUAGGGUUUUUAUGGUUUUGGGUCUUACGUUUAAGACUUCCUCUUUUCCUAAUUGAAUACCCUUUAUUUCUUUCUCUUGCCUGAUUGCCCUGGCCAGAACUUCCAGUACUAUGUUGAGUAGGAAUGGUGAGAGAGGGCAUCCUUGUCUUGUGCUGGUUUUCCAAGGGAAUGCCUCUAGUUUUUGCCCAUUCAGUAUGAUAUUGGCUGUGGGUUUGUCAUAAAUAGCUCUUCUUAUUUUGAGAUGCGUUCCAUCAAUACCUGGUUUAUUGAGAGUUUUUAGCAUGAAGGGCUGUUGAAUUUUGUUGAAUGCCUUUUCUGCAUCUAUUGAGUUAGGGAGGAUUCCCUCUUUUUCUAUUGUUUGGAAUAGUUUCAGAAGGAAUGGUACCAGCUCCCUUUUGUACCUCUGGUAGAAUUCGGCUGUGAAUCCAUCUGGUCCUGGACUUUUUAUGGUUGGUAGGCUAUUAAUUACUGCCUCAAUUUCAGAACUUGUUAUUGGUCUAUUCAGGAACUCGACUUCUUCCUGGUUUAGUCUUGGGAGGGUGUAUAUGUCCAGGAAUUUAUCCAUUUCUUCUAGAUUUUCUACUUUAUUUGCGUAGAGUUGUUUAUAGUAUUCUCUAAUGGUAGUUUGUAUUUCUGUGGUAUCGGUGGUGAUAUCCCCUGUAUCAUUUUUUAUUGCAUUUAUUUGAUUCUUCUCUCUUUUCUUCUUUAUUAGUCUGGCUAGCAGUCUAUCUAUUUUGUUGAUCUUUUCAAAAAACCAGCUCCUGGAUUCAUUGUUUUUUUCGUGGUCUCUAUCUCCUUCAGUCCUGCUCUAAUCUUAGUUAUUUCUUGUCUUCUGCUAGCUUUUGAAUUUGUUUGCUCUUGCUUCUCUAGGUCUUUUAAUUGUGAUGUUAGGGUGUUGAUUUUAGAUCUUUCCUGCUUUCUCUUGUGGGCAUUUAGUGCUAUAAAUUUCCCUCUACACACUGCUUUAAUUUUGAAAUGGAGUUUUGCUCAGUUUCCCAGGCUAGAGUGCGGUGGCAUGAUCUCAGCUCACUGCAACCUCUGCCUUCUGGGUUCAAGUGAUUCUUGUGCCUCAGCCUCCCAAGAAACUGGGACUACAGGCAUGUGCCACCACACCCGGCUAAUUUUUGUAUUUUUAGUAGAAACAGGGUUUCACCAUGUUGGCCAGGCUGGUCUCGAACUCCUGACCUCAAGUGAUCCUCCUGCCUCGGCCUCCCAAAGUGCUGGGAUUACAGGCGUGAGCCACCAUGCCCAGCCCCAUGUCCUUUUUAAUGCCUGGAUUGACUUUGUGGGACAUGAGGCCAAGGUACCUUUUAAGAUGUCACCUGUAUAGCAUACUAGUAGUGAAUGUAGGCUUUGAAGUCAGAUGCAUCUGGCUGUGAGCUGUGACUAGUCAUAUACUAGUUGUGUCAUUUUGAACAGGUUACCUAACCUCUGGCUCCUCAGUUUGUUCAUCUGUUUAAAAAUUGUGGGAAUAACAGUUCCUGCUGGGUCAUUGCAAGAUGUCAGUGAGACGUGUCAAGUGCUUAGAAUAGGGCUUGGCAUAAGUAGAGUCUCAGUAGGGUAGGUGUUAUUUAAUCCCAGAAAUAACUGACAACUUUGGAAGAUGAGAGUGAAUGUCUCCGAUCAUUAAUUUAUUUAACAAAUACUUAUCUAGUACUAUGUGCCCGGCGCUGUAGACACUGCCAUGUUUUAUCUCAUUCAAUAUUCACAGUGACUGCCCAGUGAAUGGUAUUGCCUCCAUCCUCUGAGAAGGUAAAGAGCCUAUCCCAGACCCCACGAGUGGAGGCGUCAGGGAGGGGUUCUUGGCAGGAGAUGGGUCUUGUAGAAAGGCUUCUGCUUUGCUUUCACUCACGGCCUGUGGCCAGUUUGCUCAGACAGCUCCCAUCAGGACACCAUUGGCAGCUUUUGCAUGACCCUGCCUCCCAGGGUCUUCCUGCGUUUUUCCUUAAGUUGCCUUAUUCUUUGGUUGUUUCCCUACUUGUUUUUGUUAGACUGUGGGAGGAAGAAAUCCAUUUCAAAUCUGCUGAAACCUGUUACCAAGCAACAGCAGUGAUUAAAAGCAACCUGAUGAGUGAGUAAAGAAUUAGGGUUUCAGACCUGUAGUUAAUGAUGGUCUCUGUCUCCCUGCUGCCCUGCAUUCCCUUCCCUUCCGUUCACUGCUGGGUGAAGGAGGGCUUGCUGCAUUUUGGAAGUUAAGGGAACCAAUAAGGUGACUCUUUUGCAGAUUGGAAUAUGGUGCUCAGCCAGCCAUAUGGAAGCACUGUCCUGGCGUGAUCUGCCCUGGGCUGUUGGCUCUCUGAGUGCUGUCUUGGGAGGAGCACUGCCCUUCAGAACAGAAGAGAUGGCUUCCAGUCCCCUCUCCCCCUUCUCCCAGUCUCUCUGAGGCUGCUUGUUGGGUAUUGGGCGUGCUGUGUACUAACUCACUCCCGUCUCUUGUCUCAUUAUCUGAAAUGCAUCCCCUUUUGCAGAAAGGGCUCAAACGGAGCCUUCAGUUCUGCUCCUCUGCAUAGCCGUAGCUCAGAUCCUAGCUCAAGAUGUCUUGUCUGGGAAGGGCAAAACAUGGUCCCCAGUGUAGCAUUUUCACUGGGUUGAUUAUCUCAGUGGUGGAUCAUCUAUCACCCUUGUGUGGUGACUUUGUGAAUUAUCUGCCUGAGUGCCACUUCCCUUCCACCCUAAUCACUGCAGGCUCAGGGAGCAAGAAAUAAAAUCAUGAAAUGCAUUCCAAAUAAAAUUACCUUUUGGCUGGGUGCAGUGGCUCACACCUGUAAUCUGAGCACUUUGGGAGGCUGAGGUGGGUGGAUCGCUUGAGGUCAGGAGUUCAAGACCAGCCUGGCCAACAUGGCAAAACCCCAUCUCUACAAAAAAUACAACAGCAAAAAAAUCAGCCAGGCUAGCUGGUGUGCGCCUAUAAUCCCAGCUACUUGGGAGGGAGGCUGAGGCACAAGAAUUGCUUGAACCCAGGAGGUGGAAGUUCAGUGAGCCGAGAUCGCACCCCUGCACUCCAGCCUGAGCAACAGAGUGAGACUCUGUCUCAAAAAUAAAUAAAAAAAAAAAUCACUUUUUGAUACUUCUGUUAAAAUAGAUAAUAAGGAACCAUAUCUUAAAGUGUGGAGGAUCUGGCUUGGCUUCUGUUUUUGAUAGCUCUAUGAAAGUGACAGAUUUGCAUCAUGAGACUUAGUGGAAUGAAUUGGGAAAUUGAAGGGCAGCCCAGUGGCUAUGGAUUCUAUUUUCUAUGGGACUGUCUACGCCAGGCUUUAUUUUCUCUUUGCUCAGAUAACUUCUGACUAGAGUCGACGGUAGGAUUAUAAAUGGUUUAAAAUACGUAUUCUCAAACCUCAUUUUCAGCAUAUAAAUUUUUAAGAAUCAGUGUUUAAAGGUACGUGAAACCAUUUGCUAGAUUUUUGUCCUAGUUUUUUUUUUUUAAUUUAAAAAUCUUAAGUUUUUUUUAGUAAGCUUAAGAUGUCCAGUAGUUUAUUUGCAGACAGCAUUUUUAAAAAGUGAAUAGAUGUUUAACUGAAGUUAAAUACAAAUUUAUGUCUGUGUAACUCUUGGUAAGAUAUAACAAAACCUAGACAUCUAAAUUUUUUGGAAAUUUUUAUUUUAAAAGUUUGUUGGGAGGUAAAAUUGUGUGACUUUACCUUCUGGUUAAUAGUUUUAUAGUUAAGAAGAAAGUCCAGCGAAGUUUACUUGAUCUCAGUUGCACUCAAGAAUAGGGGAUUUAGUUCCACUUUGGUUAUUUUCACUUCUACCCUAAAUUCAUAGUCCCUGAUACUUAAGCUUUACCCUUGGCUUACCAGUUUUCAUUGCAGCGAGUAAAUGGGGAGUAGCAGAGCCUUUGUUAAUGUAAAUUGACAAAAAGUAUGUCCUUUUCUAGCAGGAGCAGAUAAACUGAUAAUGGUCUUAGAAAUGUAGAAAAUGAUUUUUUGUAGACAGGAUGAUCUGUCUAGAUUGUAGCAAAUGAUGGUACAUAUUCACAACAAAGUUGUGCCACUACAUUUAAUAAACAGCCACAAACAACAAAAGGACAACUGGUCCCCGAUAUAAAUGGACUAGCUACCUGGACAUAAUAUCCUUGUGAGGCAUCCUUAAAGGACAAAUUGCAGCUGGUAUUUGGGUGAAUGUUGUUGCUCUGUGCCUGUUGAAUGUCCAUGCUACAAGAAGUUAUGAGCCUUGUUCUAAGUACAGAUGAACCUUGUAUUUGUGUAAUCUCCCAAGGGAGAGCUAUGGUUUACAUUCAAUUUUUUGGUCUUUCUGCUAUGAAACGUGUUUAUUUUGCCUCUGUCAAUGUGUUUGCAACCUUAAGUAAGGAAAGGGAAAAAAAAAAUAGCCCUCUGAACUCUGAUCUUUUGCCGCUUCUGUAGAUUUUGAUUGUGAAGUUGGGAGUGAGGACAUUCAAAAGCCCAUGGUGAAUGCAUAUGCCUUUAGAAUAUUGUGCCUGUUUUAAAAUGUUUGAGCUUUUAAAAUACGUUGUUAAAACAUGAAUCCAUUUUUGUAAUUGUAUAAAUACUCAUAACUAAUUUUGAAUGCUACUGAUUGUGUAACUGAAUUUUUGUAUCCAAAAAUACAUUCUUGAGUACUACUUUUCCUACCUUGAAAAUCUAUUUCAUUUACUAAAUAUUGUUUUCUUUAUGCUAACUUAACUUUAAAAGGAAUGUUGCCAAGCUGUCUCUCCUCCCCCAUCACAAUUGUUAGUUUUUUUUGCUUUCUUUCUUCAAUAAAUGAUAGCAUUAUGAUCUUUAA